GGCCAGGCGUGAUGGAAAGGAAUGAGGGAUGGGGAGAUUUCUUCUUCAAGAAAGCUGGGAAGAAGAGAGGCCAGAGAUAGAGAGACAGGUAGGACAUCAUCUGGGCCCAGGCCUUGGGAACUUGGGGCUCCAGCAAAGGGUUGCUGAGGGACAGGAGAAAGCCCAGAUAAGCAAUGCCUUGGGAUUUUUGGCCUGGUUAACUGGGGCAAGGGGCAGGCAGACGGGUGCAGGCUAGAAAGGUUUGUUUUGGAGGCUUGAAACAUUACAUGUUAUCUUCUUGAUCUCCACCAUCAAAUAAUUGUGCCUUAAGGAAGGCAGAGUUAUUUACUCUGACUCUGAAGAGUCAUCAAAAUGAUAAUAAUAAUAAUAAUACAUCUUUUGUGCACUUUUAUUGGCUGCACAACAACAUUGUAGCAACAACAGAAAUUUAAAAACAAAAAGAAAACAAUAGAUACCCAGCACAGAGGGUCACUGCUGCCAGACCAGCUGCCGCUCUCCCAGGCCGAGUGUCUUGGGUGGCUUUGGCAGGGAUCUGGCCUGAGCUGUGGGGGUGGGUGUUUCCUCUCAUGCCCCCUGCCCUCACCUCAGAGAUAAAGGAGAAGGGACUGGGCCAAGAAGAGGACCAACUGGUUUCUGAGAAUGGUUUGAAAGACACCGGAGAGAGGCCAGGAACAGGGACAGCUUGGUCCCGGGAGCCUCCCACGUUCAUCCUCCCAGGAUUCCAAGGCAUCUUGCUGACUUGCUGAGCCACCUAGGGCAGGUCCCACCAACUGGCUUAGGCUCAGACACCCCAGACUUUAUAAUCCCUUCUCUGGGGUGCUCAAAGAGCAGGUGUUGGCACCAGGGGCCUGGGCCACAGCAAAACCGUGGAGCUCAGCAAGUCCUGAGUAUGAGUGAUGGCACAGGCAUUCCUGCAAUUCAAGGGGCAGGAAGGGAGCCAUUUGUGGGGGAGGCUCCGUGUCCCUUGGAGCCCCAGAAAAGCAUCUGGCAUCCCGAGGGAGAAACACAUAAUCCCCAGCCCUGCGGGCCUCAAUGGCUUCAUCUGAAUGGCUGUCGUCUGGCAGCCGUGCAGCAGUAGACACGCAGCAUGGGCAGGUUUUAAACAAGCAGGGUAGGGAGUCCCAGAGAGGGUCCCUUCAGACAGGGCUGGAGUAGAGGCAUCUGAGCAGCCAGGGGCCAGAUGAGGGACAGGGAGAAGGCCCUGAGUUUAAUGGCGAGGCAGGGCCUGGGUGGGCAACUGUAAGGGAGGUGACAAGGCCAUCACGAUCUAGUGUAUCAGGACUUUGGGAAACUGGCAGGGACGGCCAAGGUGGGCGUGCCCCAGGAUCCUCCACCCUGUGCACUGGGCUGUGAAGGAGACUGAGACGGACAAUCUUCUUUCCUGCCCUCAAAGAACCCCCAGUCUGAGGGCAGACAGGUCCUCUGUAAAGGGCAGGGACAGGCUGAGGAAGGAGGGCUCCCUCUGGGAGCUGUGGGGGCAAGGUGGGCCUCUUGCAUUAGAAGGACCUGUGGCUGUCCUCAGAACCUCAAGCUCCCUCUAGGCCUAGAGGUCUGGACUGAGUGCUCUGCCCUUGGGAGUUCAGCUUCCAGGGCUGGUGACAAAGAGAAAGGGGAGGUUUGGGAGGGGCUAAGGAGGCACCAUGGUUGUCAGCAGGCGCCCAGAGCGGAGGCCACCGAGGGACCCCAGGUGCUUCCCAGGGCAGUGCUAAGCAGGCAUCAUGGGCUCCCACAGACCUGGCUCGGGGGCCAUGCUCUGCCCAGCACCCUGUCCUGCAGCCCUGGUGUCCUUGGGGGUGGAGGGGGAGCCUCUGCGCUACAGCGUGGGUGAGUUCCAGAUUCUCAUGGAUGGCGUGUCCACCGCGUGCCAGGCCUGGAGCGGAGCUUGGACUCUUUCUCAUUGACUCCCUAGAAGCUUGGGAGCCCUGGGCUCUAGUCUCUGUACAAGAAGGGGGAUUGGGGCUGGCACAGAUUGGGAGGGGUCUUGAAGCUGCCCUUUCACAAAGCAUUUUUGAUAAGAUUGGGAAAAGCCAACUAUCCCUAUCAAAGACUGCUGGGGAGGAGGGAUUCGUGGGAUUAGGAGAGCUGAAAGUCCUCCUUCCUCACACAGUUGUGCCCUGAAUAAGAAGAAUCAAGCCCUGUGCUAAGGGACUUUCUUGUAUUCUUUCCUUUUAUCUUCAUAUCAGUAGCAGGGAAAACAAAUCUAUCACUCCUAUUUGGUAGAGGAAAUGGAGCUCAGAGAGGGUUAGUGAUUUUCUCAGAGUCACACAGCUGGUAAGAGGUGGAACUCUUAACUGGCCACACUGCCUCUUUGGGACCUAGAUAGCAUCAUGCAGUCUGGUCUUCCAGGUCUGGCCCCCACAAGUCUGGCCAGCCCCUGCCUCCCUUUCAUCUAACUGCAGACACUGGCAGCCCCUCUGGGGAGCUCUUUGAGUCUUGUACACAGGAAUCAGGGUUCACUCUGGAGCCCUCGGAGGCUCCCAGAUCUCUUUGAGGUCCCAAAAAGUUUGAGGUCCUGAGCUCUGGUCCCCAGGCUGAGCUCUGAGCUCUCCAGAUGGCUGUACUCCCAGGAAGCAGCUGUGCGAAGUCAGGCCACCGAGACACUGGAAUCUGACCUUCACACAAAGGCAGCCUUGUACUGGGCCCUGGAGACACAUUACUUUUUACUUUCUAGGCCUUUCUAGAUAGAGCUUGAAGCCCAGCAGGAGAAGGGCAGCAUCGAGACCACAGAGAGGGGAGGGCACCCGGGGUGAGCAGCUGCUGGGGAUGAAACUGCUGGAGGUGCUGGCCAGGGCUGGCUCCCCACCCGCUUUCUCCCUAGGAAACUCCCACACCCACUAAGGAGCUUUUGCAAUUGGGAAGCUAGGUGCUCAGCCCCACUUGUCUCCAGUCCAGUGAAGCCCUUUGUGGGUCAAGGGAUUUGCUGGGCCUCCCUCGGUUCGUCACUCCCACCCUUCCCAAAUGUUGCAAGGGGUGGUGUUUCAGGCUGGAGCUAUGCGCUAGGGAGCCAGAAAGAGGCCUGAUACAAUGCUUGUCCUCAAGAAGCUCACAGUUUGAGGCCGGGUAGCAGGAGGAGGCCGUUGGGACAGUGGAAGGCAAGAGGACCUGCCUGUCCCCGCAGCCUCCGAUGGGGGCCGGCAGGAAAGGCUUUCCAAGGGUCAGAGGAAAUGAGUGCCAGUGAUUCCUUCUCCAUGAUAUGGAAACAGGUAAUCCCGGCCCUGCCAGCCAAAAUGAGUGGAACCUCUGGGGGUCCUCAGAGAAACAUUUUCCGCAGGGGUCAAGGCACCCACCCAGCCCCUGCCUGGACAGCCUCAGACACUGCCUGGGUGUCCCCUCCUAGGACCCUGCCAUGUGGGGCAGGUCUGGGGCAGGCCAGCCCAGGGCUUCUGGCUGGGAUGCCCGGGUUCUUGCUCAGACCCGGCUUCUCUCCAGUGGAUGGAGACCCAGCCUGAGGUCUCCUGCACAUCUCCUGAGCAUGCUCACCUUUACAGGGGCAGGUAAAGCCCAUCUCAGGUCCCUUACCCCGGUGGUCCAGGCCUGGACAAGUGGAAUCCUAGAGGCAAUUUUAAAAAGCUAAAACAAUGACUGUGGAGAAGCGUAUAGAGAACAUCUUGUCUACCCCAAUUGUAAUUCAGAUGGGGAAACUGAGGCCCAGGGUCAUUCUGCUGUGGUGGCCAGAACUCAGAGCUCUUCAGUCCCCAUUGAGAAGGCCGGGAGUGGCAGCUGCAGGGGCCCUCUCCCCUCAGACACAGAGGAACUACUGAACAGCUGACAGACCCUUCUGUGCUAGGUCUUGUCCUUAUCUCUCUUCAUGUCCUGGGGCCAAUGUGGCCUCUUCCUCUUCUGUAUCCCUGAGAGUGCCUUGCAUUGGGCUGGCCCUCAGCACAGGGUCCCGUGUUGGAGAGAGGGGCCCUCCUGGGGCUGGUUCCUGCCUGGCCUUUGGAGGAGGGCCUCUGGGGUCAGUGCCCUGCAGGACCGUUCUCGGAGAGAGAUCUGUCCUAGGCCUGAGACCCACCUCUUCCUCAACACCAGUUAUUCCUCCAUCUGCACAAGAAGCUACUUUCCUGCAGCCUUUCCCACAGACCACGGAAAACAGCCCCAGCCUCCCGCUCUCUGCUCUUGUGUUGUUUUCCUUCCCGGCUAAUUGAGUGACUGCCUUUGCUCUUUAGACGCCUUUAUUCCAGAACCCCAGAGAACACAGCUCCCUGCCUGCCCAGUGGCCCCCAGCAUAAAGGGUGGAUUGAUAAGAUACAAGCCAGGGUCAGGCCAAGACAAGUGGCAGAGGGAGGAAGCGGCAGAGGGAGAGGGAGGCGGCAGAGAGUGCCAACCUUGCCUGGGAAAGCCUACCCCCCAGCUCUCAGCUGACUUGGCACUUGGUGGGCGGGCAGUGUGCUGGUGGUGCUGCAUUGGCAGCAGGCAGCGAGCUUUCUGGGUUCUCCACUGCGCUGUAGAUCUAGUCGUUGGUUGCCUUUUGGAGUCAGCUCCUGUUGGGAUCUGGGUGCCUUGCUGGGCAACAGAGACCUUGAUUGUGUCCUGGCCCCGUUCUUGGCUGUUACUACAGCAGUGAUCUUAGUUUGGGCAUGGGACAGAGCUGAUGGUUGCACUGAUCUUAGUUUGGGCAUGGGACAGAGCUGAUGGUUGUGCCCUGUUGGUGGAGCACAAAGGGGAGAUGAGGACUACUUUAAGGACUGGCAGUCAUCCUGAUUUCCUAAGUCUCUCGAUACAGAUCUUUUCAGUGUGGUCUAUGCAUUUCUGUAUGCCCUUUUUUGCUCCCCUUUUCACUUGAUGUUAUACUGUGAACAUUUCCAUAUGUCAUUAAAUAUUCUUUUUGUACUUUAUUUUAAUGGCUGCAUGGGAAUCCAUGAUACGGCUCUACCAUAAUGAACUGAAUAAGAGACCAGUCCCCUGUUGGACAUUCGGGUUGUUUCCAAUGGCUUUGCUAAUAGACACGUUGCUGUAUGGAUAUCCAUCUCCACAUUCUCGCUGUACAUGUCUCUGAUUGCUUCCCUUGAGUAACUUCCAGAAAGUAUGAUUGCUAAGUGCAAGGAUGUUUCUGUUUCAAGCCUUUGGAUAUAUAUUGCCAGUUGCCCCCAACAAAGCUGUACCAGUUCAUGUUCUGCACUGCACUGCACCUUCCAGACAGUGGAUAUUGUCUGUUUGCCUGAUUGUAUUUUUGCUGCUUCAAGUUCUUUCCUUUUAGGAGAAACCUAGGGAGAGAGGGAGGUUAGGAGAUGAGUUCAGAUGGCUUCAGGAGAUGUGGGUUAUUGUGAGGAAAGGCAGGGAAGAAAAGAAGCUUAGAAAGAGGCUAGGAGGAGGCCGGGAGUGGUGGCUCACGCCUGUAAUCCUACCACUUUGGGAGGCUGAGGUGGGCAGAUCAUGAGGUCAGGAGAUCGAGACCAGCCUGGCCAACAUAGUGAUACCCCGUCUCUACUAAAAUACAAAAAAUUAGCUGGGCGUGGUGUCACGCACCUGUAGUCCCAGCUACUCGGGAGGCUGAGGCGGGGGAAUCGCUUGAACCCAGGAGGCAGGGGUUGCAGUGAGCCGAGAUAGUGCCACAGCACUCCAGCCUGGUGACAGAGCAAGACUCUGUCUCAAAUAGUAAUAAUAAUAAUAAUAAUAGGAAAGAACAUAAAAGUAAAAAGAAAAAGCCUAGCAGGGAAUGGGAAGAAUGGACCUUCCUGGCUCCCUGCUCAGGUGACAACCAGCAUUGCUGCAAUUCAGUUUCUCCCUGCCCUACUGCCGCCACCUGCUUCUGUGCACUCCACUCACUAUGCUGUGACUUCCACCACCCCAUUGUCUCAGCUCAGCCAUCCUGAUCUCUGCAAGUGGCUUCCAAACUCUGCAGGAGAGACUCUAAUUUUCUGUCACCACCUACAGGGAGCACUCCCACUGAGCAGUGCUCCUGCACAGCAACUUCAUGAGCCUCUGGCCAGGGCUUGCAGCUCCGGUCUCAUGCAUGUUGUCGGGGUCGCAGGGCCAAUGUCCAAGGCUCAACAGCUGUGGGCAACCCCUUCUGACCGUUCUGCCUUGCAUUUGGCGUACCUUGCCAGUAGCUAAAACCCAGGCCCAGCCCUUCUAACUCAUUGUCCAGAGACUUCUUCUUCUAUAGAGAGGGAGAUUGGCAGAGGACACGGUGUGAGCAGAGCCCACGGGUGGGAACACAUGGACAUGAGAAGAAGGGGGAGGAUUGCACACCCCAGGCUAGAAGAUGCAUCUGUCUUCCCUUCUUUCAGCUCUGAAGGGCAGGAGUGAGCUUGGCAGCUGGCACCCAAGGCUGAGGCCACUGAGCUGUGGUGGGCCCAGGUCAGAAGGACAAUGAGCAGGGCAGGCCCUACCUAAGUCUCUCAGGGGUGCAAGAUGGGAAAGGAGGCUGGCGUGUCCUGCUUGGGUAGAUACCCGCUCUGUGAGCCUGUCUCUGUGCUUAAGCACAAUGUGUCCUGUGUCCUCAUUGGCCUCCCUGGGGGGCAAGGGUGAGGUGGGGGAGAGAUGAAGGCCUGAGUCCUCUAGACACACAGUCACUGGGUCUCCAGCCCUCCUGGGACUAGGGUGGGGCAGAGUUCAGCUCAUUCUUCCCCAAAGAAGAGGCCCCUGGCCUCUGCUGGAGGCCGGGUUGCUGCUGGUAGCCAGGACCCAGAGAGGAGGGAAUCUGACUUCCAGAGCUCCAGGGUGGUGGGAGAGGCAGCCCCGACCAUGACCCCAUCCUCCAUUAGGCUCAGGAUGGGAGUCUUUAGUGAGGAGGCAACACGUGGUCCUUGAAGAGCGGUAAAGUGUGGGCAUGUGAUGGAGGGAAGGGCAUUGCAGGCAGAGUCGCAGCACAGGCAAAGGCACAGAGACGGGGAACCAAAGGGAACUGGGAGCAGUUCAGGUUGGCUGUAAGGAAAGGUGUAUGUUGAGGCUGGGAAAGGUAAGCGAGCCCCUUGGGGAGGGCCUGCCUUAGAAGCCCUGGUAUAGACGUCUCCCUGUGGUCAAUGAGAGCCAUCGGGGGCUUUUGAGCAGGUCAGACCUGGAUUUAGCAAGGUCACUCUGGGAGUCUCAGGAGUGUGGGAAAAGGCCGGUGGCUGGAGGUCAUGGCUGCCCAAGGUCACCCAGCCUGAACCUGUCACAGGACUUGGCGGGAGGCAUGAUAGUCCUUUCCCAGAGGAGAUGGGAGAUGUGGUGCCGGGGUCUUCCUUGAAGUUCACCGUGAGAGGCAGCACCCCUGUGGGAACAGCAGACUUGGGUAUGGAACUGUGGGGGUUUGGAUGCCAGCUCUGCCACUCAACUCUUUAGUUGGGAGGUGACAGUGGUGAUGGGCAAAGAAUGGCAUGGCGCAUGGCAGGGGCUCAGUAAGCAGUAAGCAAGAGAUGAUCGGGGCCUCAGCGAGGGCAGGGGCAGCCUCCUUCCCACCAGAAUCUCCUCUUCCAGCUGGUCUAGGGGCUCAGACAGGUCCUGCUGGCUCAGCUGAGCUUGUGCAGAGAAAGGGCUGGGUCAUGCAGCUGGCCAGGAGGCCUUGUCACCCUUCCCAAGGGUGACAAGGGGUCCUCCAGAGCUAGGGCUCUUGUCCCUGUCAUGAAACAGCUGGACUAAUAGGAGACUGACAUUGCAGACCUAUGAACCUUCCUUCCCUUCCCAUGCCUCAUUCCCUCCUUCCAGGAAGGAUAUGAGAUGACCUGACACAAAAGCACAGGCUCCAUGGAAGAGGAAACAGGAAAAAGACAGAACCAUGUAGCUGAUGGGAGAGGAGAAAUUAGAGGAGGCGCUGUGGACGACUCGGGCCGAUGGGCGGGUGCGCCUGCGCAUAGACCCCAGCUGCCCACAGCUUCCCUACACUGUGCAUCGGAUGUUCUACGAGGCCCUGGAUAAGUAUGGGGACCUCAUCGCUUUGGGCUUCAAGCGCCAGGACAAGUGGGAACACAUCUCCUACUCCCAAUACUACCUGCUCGCCCGCAGAGCCGCCAAGGGCUUCCUGAAGCUCGGCCUGAAGCAGGCCCACAGUGUGGCCAUCCUCGGCUUCAACUCCCCGGAGUGGUUCUUCUCGGCAGUGGGCACAGUAUUUGCAGGUGGCAUCGUCACUGGCAUCUACACCACCAGCUCCCCAGAGGCCUGCCAGUACAUCGCUUAUGACUGCUGCGCCAAUGUCAUCAUGGUCGACACGCAGAAGCAGCUGGAAAAGAUCCUGAAGAUCUGGAAACAGUUGCCACAUCUAAAGGCAGUCGUGAUAUAUAAAGAACCUCCUCCAAACAAGAUGGCCAAUGUGUACACGAUGGAGGAAUUCAUGGAGCUGGGGAAUGAAGUGCCUGAGGAAGCCCUGGACGCCAUCAUUGACACCCAGCAGCCCAACCAGUGCUGUGUGCUAGUCUACACUUCCGGCACCACUGGGAACCCCAAGGGCGUGAUGCUGAGUCAAGACAAUAUCACGUGGACGGCACGGUACGGCAGCCAGGCCGGUGACAUCCGGCCGGCAGAAGUCCAGCAGGAGGUGGUAGUCAGCUACCUGCCCCUCAGCCAUAUUGCCGCCCAGAUCUACGACCUGUGGACAGGCAUCCAGUGGGGGGCCCAGGUUUGCUUUGCCGAACCCGACGCCCUGAAGGGGAGCCUGGUGAACACGCUGCGGGAGGUGGAGCCCACAUCACACAUGGGGGUGCCCCGGGUAUGGGAGAAGAUCAUGGAGCGCAUCCAGGAGGUGGCGGCUCAGUCUGGCUUCAUCCGGCGAAAGAUGCUGCUGUGGGCCAUGUCGGUGACCUUGGAGCAGAACCUCACCUGCCCCGGCAGCGACCUGAAGCCCUUCACAACCAGACUGGCAGAUUACCUGGUGCUAGCCAAGGUUCGCCAGGCACUGGGAUUUGCCAAGUGUCAAAAGAACUUCUAUGGAGCGGCCCCCAUGAUGGCAGAGACACAGCACUUCUUCCUGGGUCUCAACAUCCGCUUGUAUGCGGGCUACGGCCUCAGUGAGACCUCAGGCCCCCACUUCAUGUCCAGUCCCUACAACUACCGGCUGUACAGCUCAGGCAAGUUGGUGCCCGGCUGUCGGGUGAAGCUGGUGAACCAGGACGCAGAGGGCAUUGGCGAGAUCUGCCUGUGGGGCCGCACCAUAUUCAUGGGCUACCUGAACAUGGAGGACAAGACUUGUGAGGCCAUCGACGAGGAAGGCUGGCUGCACACGGGUGAUGCUGGCCGCCUGGACGCCGAUGGCUUCCUCUACAUCACUGGGCGCCUCAAAGAAUUAAUCAUCACAGCUGGUGGGGAGAAUGUGCCCCCUGUGCCCAUCGAGGAGGCCGUGAAGAUGGAGCUGCCCAUCAUCAGCAACGCCAUGCUCAUUGGGGACCAGAGGAAGUUCCUGUCCAUGCUGCUCACCUUGAAGUGCACUCUGGACCCAGACACCUCUGACCAGACUGAUAAUCUGACUGAACAAGCUAUGGAGUUCUGCCAGAGGGUGGGCAGCAGAGCCACCACAGUGUCCGAGAUCAUAGAGAAGAAGGAUGAGGCCGUGUACCAGGCCAUCGAAGAGGGGAUCCGGAGGGUCAACAUGAACGCGGCGGCCCGGCCCUACCACAUCCAGAAGUGGGCCAUUCUCGAGAGAGACUUCUCCAUUUCGGGUGGAGAGUUGGGUCCCACGAUGAAACUGAAACGGCUCACAGUUUUGGAGAAGUACAAAGAUGGAGUCUCACUCUGUUGCCCAGGCUGGAGUGCAGUGGCACGAUCCCAGCUCACCACAACCUCUGCCUCCUGGGUUCAAGCGAUUCUCCUGCCUCAGCGUCCUGAAUAGCUGGAAUUACAAGUGCAUGCCACCAUACCCAACUAAUUUUUGUAUCUGAUCUAUUUUUGGAGGCUGGGACACAAAUACGAAAGAAAUAUUUAAAUCAUUAACUCUUUUUUUUUUUUUUAAGAGACGGGGUCUCACUAUGUGGCCCAGGCUGGUCUUGAACUCAGAGGCUAAGGUGAUCCUCCUGCCUCAGCCUAUAGCUGCAACUACAGGCAUGCACCACCACACCUGCCUAAAUCAUUAACUCUUAAACCUCCCUCUUUAGGAAAGAAAGCCUCCCAUACAACUGAUCUGUUCUACCAGCUUAUCCUUUCUUUCCUGCAUACAGACCCCAAUAUAUUUAAUUCUCUUUAUCUUUCCAUCCUACACAAUAAAAGGGCCCACUAUGUAAUUCAGGCACCUCUCUACUGGGCUGUAGAUUAUAACUUCCCAAAUAUAACUUUAAAGAAUAAGAAAAUCAUAUGACCUCCAAUGUGACUAUCAGGCUGUUAAAAACAAGCCUGAAUUUCUUGUAUUUUGGCCACACGAUAUAAUUUCAAAUUACAGAAUUUUUUUAAAAGAAGGGACCAACUUUGAAGAUAUUACGCUAAGUGAAAUAAGCCAGACUCAAAGGACAAAUACUGUAUGAUUCCACUUACAUGAGGUACCUAGAGUAGUCAAAUUCAUAGAGACAGGAAGCAGAAUGGCAGGUGUCAGAGGAUGGGAGGGGGAAGGGAAAGUUACUGUUUAACGGGUGCAGAGUCUCAGUUUGAGAAAAUGAAACUGGUCUGGAGAUGACUGAUGGUGAUGGUUACAUUACAAUGUGAAUGUACUUAACAUUAUUGAACUGUAUACCUAAAUACGGCUAAAAUGGCAAAUUUUAUGUUAUGCAUAUUUUUCACAAUUUUUGUUAAAAAGGACCUCAAAUUAGG